AGUGCACAGCGGGACCAGGCAGAGUUCGGGGAAAGCGUCGGAGUUCGGGAGACCAGGGUCCAGCAUGGGUUUCAGCACAGCAGACGGCGGGGGCGGCCCAGGCGCCCGGGAUCUGGAAUCUCUUGAUGCCUGUAUCCAGAGGACGCUCUCUGCCUUGUACCCACCGUUUGAAGCCACGGCAGCCACGGUGCUCUGGCAGCUGUUCAGCGUGGCCGAGAGGUGCCACGGUGGGGACGGGCUGCACUGCCUCACCAGCUUCCUCCUCCCAGCCAAGAGGGCCCUGCAGCACCUGCAGCAGGAAGCCUGUGCCAGGUACAGGGGUCUGGUCUUCCUGCACCCAGGCUGGCCGCUGUGCGCCCAUGAGAAGGUGGUGGUGCAGCUGGCGUCCCUGCACGGAGUCAGGCUCCAGCCCGGGGACUUCUACCUGCAGGUCACGUCGGCGGGGAAGCAGUCAGCUAGACUGGUCUUGAAAUGCCUGUCCCGGCUGGGAAGAGGCACAGAGGAAGUCACCGUCCCUGAGGCCAUGUAUGGCUGUGUCUUCACGGGGGCGUUCCUGGAGUGGGUGAACCGGGAGCGGCGCCAUGUCCCCCUGCAAACCUGCUUGCUGACCUCAGGCUUGGCCGUCCACCGAGCCCCGUGGAGCGACGUCACUGACCCUGUCUUUGUCCCCAGCCCUGGAGCCAUCCUGCAGAGCUACUCCAGCUGCACAGGUCCUGAGCGGCUGCCCAGCAGCCCCUCAGAGGCCCCAGUCCCCACCCAAGCCACAGCAGGCCCCCAUUUCCAGGGAAGCGCCUCUUGCCCCGACACCCUGACCUCACCCUGCCGCCGAGGGCAUACGGGCAGCGACCAGCUCAGGCACCUUCCUUAUCCAGAAAGAGCCGAGCUGGGAAGCCCCAGGACCCUGUCUGGAAGCUCAGACAGGGACUUCGAAAAGGUCAGCCCCUCAGAGCAGGGCCCACGGAUGCCCCCUGAGAACUGUGGGGGGUCGGGGGAGAGGCCGGACCCCAUGGACCAGGAGGACAGACCCAAGGCCCUCACCUUCCACACAGACCUGGGCAUCCCGAGCAGCAGGAGGCGGCCGCCGGGGGACCCCACUUGUGUGCAGCCUAGACGCUGGUUCAGGGAGUCGUACAUGGAAGCCUUGCGGAACCCCAUGCCCCUGGGCAGCUCUGAGGAGGCCCUCGGGGACCUGGCCUGCAGCUCCCUGACUGGAGCCAGCAGGGACCUGGGGACUGGGGCAGUAGCCAGUGGGACCCAGGAGGAAACCUCUGGCCCCCGGGGAGACCCCCAACAGACCCCAAGUCUAGAGAAGGAGAGGCACACACCCAGCCGGACAGGUCCAGGAGCUGCAGGGCGGACUCUUCCCAGGAGAUCUCGGUCCUGGGAAAGGGCACCCAGAAGCUCCAGAGGGGCCCAGGCUGCAGCCUGCCACACCUCCCACCACUCAGCAGGCUCCAGGCCUGGGGGCCACCUAGGAGGACAAGCUGUGGGGACCCCAAACUGUGUCCCAGUAGAGGGUCCCGGCUGCACCAAAGAGGAAGACGUUCUUGCAUCCUCAGCCUGUGUCAGCACAGACGGCGGCAGCCUCCAUUGCCACAACCCCAGCGGGCCUUCCGAUGUGCCUGCCCGGCAGCCACACCCCGAGCAAGAAGGGUGGCCACCCGGCACAGGAGACUUCCCCAGCCAGGUGCCCAAGCAGGUGCUGGACGUCAGUCAGGAGCUGCUGCAGUCCGGGGUCGUCACCCUCCCAGGGACCCGAGACCGUCAUGGCAGAGCAGUGGUGCAGGUCCGCACCAGGAGCCUGCUCUGGACCAGGGAACACUCGUCCUGUGCUGAGCUGACCCGCCUGCUGCUGUACUUCCAUAGCAUCCCCAGGAAAGAGGUCCGGGACCUGGGGCUGGUUGUCCUGGUGGAUGCACGCAGGAGUCCAGCUGCCCCUGCCGUCUCCCAGGCCCUCUCAGGAUUGCAGAACAACACAUCUCCUAUAAUUCAUAGUAUCUUGCUGUUGGUAGAUAAAGAAUCUGCAUUUAGGCCUGACAAGGAUGCAAUAAUUCAGUGUGAGGUCGUGAGCUCCCUGAAGGCCGUGCACAAAUUUGUUGACAGCUGCCAGCUGACCGCAGACCUCGACGGCUCCUUUCCCUACAGCCAUGGUGACUGGAUCUGCUUCCGUCAGAGGCUGGAACACUUCGCUGCAAACUGUGAAGAAGCCAUCAUUUUCCUACAGAAUUCAUUCUGCUCCCUGAACACCCACAGAACCCCAAGAACAGCCCAGGAAGUCGCCGAGUUAAUUGACCAGCAUGAGACGAUGAUGAAGCUUGUCCUGGAAGACCCACUGCUUGUGUCUCUCAGGCUGGAGGGGGGCACCGUCCUGGCGCGGCUGAGGAGAGAAGAGCUUGGCACAGAAGACAGCCGGGACACCCUGGAGGCCGCCACAAGCCUGUACGACCGAGUGGAUGAGGAGGUGCACAGGCUGGUCCUCACCUCGAACAAUCGUCUCCAGCAGCUGGAGCACCUCCGGGAGCUGGCGUCACUCCUGGAAGGGAAUGACCAGCAAUCCUGCCAGAAAGGACUACAGCUGGCGAAGGAGAACCCGCAACGUACAGAGGAAAUGGUCCAGGAUUUCAGAAGGGGCCUGAGCGCCGUGGUCAGCCAGGCUGAGUGCAGGGAGGGAGAGCUGGCCAGGUGGACCCGCUCGUCCGAGUUGUGCGAGACGGUGAGCAGCUGGAUGGGGCCCCUGGACCCGGAGGCUUGUCCCUCCUCACCCGUGGCUGAGUGUUUGAGGAGCUGUCACCAGGAGGCUACCUCGGUGGCUGCAGAGGCCUUCCCCGGGGCAGGUGUGGCAGUGCUGAAGCCUCAUGCCCUGGGGAAACCGUGGGCAUCACAGCAAGACCUGUGGCUGCAGUACCCCCAGACCCGGCUCCGUCUGGAAGAGGCCCUUUCUGAGGCUGCCCCAGACCCCAGCUUACCGCCCCUUGCCCAGAGCCCCCCAAAGCAUGAGCGUGCCCAGGAGGCCAUGAGGAGGCACCAGAAGCCACCCUCAUUCCCCAGCACGGACAGUGGGGGUGGUGCCUGGGAACCUGCGCAACCACUGUCCGGCCUCCCUGGACGAGCGCUUCUGUGUGGACAGGACGGGGAGACCCUGCGCCCAGGGCUGUGUGCUCUGUGGGACCCACUGUCCCUCCUCAGGGGCCUUCCAGGGGCAGGGGCCACCACGGCCCACCUGGAGGACAGCUCUGCCUGUUCCUCUGAGCCCACCCAGACCCUGGCCAGCCGCCCCAGGAAACAUCCCCAGAAGAAAAUGAUAAAGAAAACGCAAAGUUUCGAGAUACCUCAGCCCGACAGUGGCCCCAGGGACUCCUGCCAGCCAGACCAUACUAGUGUCUUCAGCAAGGGCCUGGAGGUAACCAGCACUGUAGCCACAGAGAAGAAGCUCCCGCUGUGGCAGCAUGCCAGGAGCCCCCCGGUCACUCAGAGCCGGAGUCUGUCCUCCCCCUCGGGGCUCCACCCUGCUGAGGAGGAUGGGAGGCAGCAGGUGGGCAGCAGCCGACUGAGGCACAUCAUGGCCGAGAUGAUCGCCACAGAGAGGGAGUACAUUCGGUGCUUAGGAUACGUCAUUGACAACUAUUUUCCAGAAAUGGAAAGAAUGGACUUGCCCCAGGGCCUUCGAGGGAAGCACCACGUUAUUUUCGGCAACUUGGAGAAGCUCCACGACUUCCACCAGCAGCACUUCCUCCGGGAGCUGGAGCGCUGCCAGCACUGCCCCUUGGCCGUGGGCCGCAGUUUCCUGAGACACGAAGAGCAGUUUGGGAUGUACGUGAUCUACAGCAAAAACAAGCCGCAGUCGGAUGCCCUGCUCAGCAGCCAUGGCAACGCCUUCUUCAAGGACAAGCAGCGGGAGCUAGGUGACAAAAUGGACCUGGCCUCCUACCUGCUGCGGCCCGUGCAGCGUGUGGCCAAGUACGCGCUGCUACUCCAGGACCUGCUCAAGGAGGCCAGCUGUGGCCUGGCCCAGGGGCAGGAGCUGGGCGAGCUCCGAGCCGCCGAGGUCGUGGUCUGCUUCCAGCUGCGUCACGGCAAUGACCUGCUGGCCAUGGACGCCAUCCGCGGCUGUGACGUGAAUUUGAAGGAACAGGGGCAGCUGAGAUGCCGGGAUGAGUUUAUCGUUUGCUGCGGGAGGAAGAAGUAUCUGAGGCAUGUGUUCCUCUUUGAAGACCUCAUCCUGUUUAGCAAGACCCAGAAGGUGGAGGGCAGCCACGACGUCUACCUGUACAAGCAGUCCUUCAAGACGGCCGAGAUCGGGAUGACAGAGAACGUCGGGGACAGUGGCUUGAGGUUUGAGAUUUGGUUUCGCAGGCGGCGGAAAUCUCAGGACACCUACAUUCUCCAAGCAAGCUCGGCAGAGGUCAAGAGUGCAUGGACCGAUGUCAUAGGGAGGAUCCUGUGGCGGCAGGCACUAAAGAGCAGAGAACUCAGAAUCCAAGAAAUGGCAUCCAUGGGUAUAGGCAACCAGCCAUUCAUGGAUGUCAAGCCCAGAGACCGGACCCCUGACUGUGCAGUGAUAAGCGACCGGGCUCCCAAAUGUGCAGUGAUGAGCGACCGAGUCCCCGACAGCAUCGUCAAGGGCACAGAGUCACAAAUGAGAGGGUCCACAGCGGUGUCCUCCUCUGACCACGCCGCCCCCUUCAAGCGACCACACUCCACCAUCUCAGACAGCAGCACCUCCUCUUCUAGCAGCCAGUCCUCCUCCAUCCUGGGGUCGCUGGGCCUGCUUGUGUCCUCCAGCCCAGCCCACCCGGGCCUAUGGAGCCCUGCCCACAGCCCCUGGUCAUCUGAUAUCAGAGCCUGCGUCGAGGAAGAUGAGCCAGAGCCAGAACUAGAGACGGGCACCCAGGCUGCAGUGUGUGAGGGGGCUCCUGCUGUGCUGCUGAGCCGCACACGCCAGGCCUGAUGACUGUCAGGGUGGCAGUGCCCAUCAUGUGGCUAGAACAAUACAGAGGGAGCAGCACGCCAGGCCUGAUGACUCUGGGGGUGGCGGUGCCCAUCGCGUGGCUGGAACGAUCCAGAGGGAAUAGCACAGCAGGUGUCCAGGUAUUUCCCAGGAUUUUAGACAUUCCCUAACAUUUUCAAACAAAUUUAUAAUUUUGUCUUAUUUAAAAAACAAACCUUCCACUUCCACCCAAGACAACAGCAUAGGAAACAGACCUAAAACAAGACAAAAAAAGACUAAACAUGAAACAAAAGAUGUCAAGACACAAGACAUUUGGCAACAAAGGACCGCGAUCCCUGAGAGACAGGAAAACGGGAGGUGAGCCCGGUGAUGGCCUCAGACCUCCCUCCGCCUUGAGAGUUUGCAGGCCUCAGUGCAGGGAGGGGCCCAGGAAGAGCCCAGCAGCCUCCGUGAGUUGAAGAGACCAAGUCAGCAGGAGUUGGCAGGUCAGAGUGCCAGAGAGAGAUGCCUGCAUGGGGAAAGACUCACCAGAUCAGCCCCUCCAGCACCUAGUGGGUUGCUACCCAUUCGCACACUCAAACAGGGAGGCUACCAAGGCUGGGAGCAACCUUUGAAAAGACCAAAGAUCAAUUCCUGGUACUCAUGUGGGCUGGGGACAGGACCCGUUCCCACCAGCCAGACUAGGGAAACUCUCAAUAGAUCAAUUCCUGAUACUCAUGUGGGCUGGGGACAGGACCCACUCCCACCAGCCAGACUAGGAAAACUCCCAAUCUGUGAGCAUUAGGUGGAGUUCUCAGAAAAUCUUGCCUCAGGAAUGGGGAUAAUUAGCCCUAGACUGAGCCCUGCUCCUGACUCGCCUACAAAAUCAUAAAAGCAAGACCUAAAAUGAUCAAACCAUUCCCAGAUAAUUCACUUUAUCCCAGAACAAAGCUCCAGAUGAUCUAGGGGUUACCAAAGUGUCCACACCCUGCAAGGUAAACUCACAGUGCCUGACCUCGGAGUGCCAGGCGUGCAGAGGAGCAGCCAAGGGCAAACACUCCAAGGAGAGUCGCCUGGCAAAGCCAACCACCCAGAGCCAGCGUCUGUGCUAGAAUCACAGAAUUCAAACUGUGGCUGAAAUCGCAGCCCAGGCGUCCAGAAAGUUAAAGUUAAGAACCUAUAAUCCCAGCACUUUGGGAGGCCGAGGCAGGCGGAUCACGAGGUCAGGAGAUCAAGACCAUCCUGGCUAACAUGGUGAAACCCCGCCUACUAAAAAUACAAAAAAUUAGCCGGGCAUGGUGUUGGCCGCCUGUAGUCCCAGCUACUUGGGAGGCUGAGGCAGGAGAAUGGCAUGAACCCGGGAGGCGGAGUUUGCAGUGAGCUGAGAUCACGCCACUGCACUCCAGCCUGGGCGACAGAGCAAGACUCUGUCUCACAAAAAAGGUUAAGAAAUGACUUAAUGGAAGAGAUUCAGAAGACCCAGACCGACCUUACAGGGAUGAGAAACUACAAUAUUGACAGUGGAAACUAUCCUGGAUGGGGUAACAGAUUGGAUUUCACAGAAGAGACCAUGAGGCACCUUGAAGACACAUCAGUGGAAACUAUUUGCAUUUGUUGGGCCUCCAGAGAGACAGAACCAAUAGGAGAUAGCUAGAUAUAUAUACAGACAGAUAGAUAGAUAGAUAGAUCGAUAGAUAGAUAGAUAGAUAGAUAGAUAGAUAGAUAGACUGACAGACAGAUGAGAGGGGCCUUAGGGGCAUUGGCUGACACAAUUUUGGCAGGUCAAGAGCCCCACAAUAGGCCAUCCACAAGCUGGAGACCCAAGGAAGCUGCUAGUGUGCCCAGUCCGAGUCCUAAAGCCUCAGAGCCAGGGAAGCCAGUGGUGUAAUUCUCAGAGGCCAAAGGCCUGAGAACCUGGGGGCCACUGGUAUAAGUCUGAGUCCAUAGACCCAGUGAACUCCAAACACAAGAGAUACGAGUGCACAUCAUAAUCAAAUUGCAUAUAACCAGUGAUAAACAGAAAAUCCUAAAACCAGUCAGAGGACAAGGGCAUGUUCUGUUGGGAGGCACAAAGCUGAUGAGGAUGGCUGACUCCUCAGGAGCAGCAUGGGUGAGAGGCAGUGGAAUGUACUAAGGAGAAAACUGCCAAAUUCACAUUCUGUACCUGACAAAAUCUUUCCGAAGCGAUGGUGACAUAAAGACAUUUUCAUACACACAGAAACUAAGAGUUUCAUCCCCAGCAGACCUGCACUACAAGAAAUGUUAAAUGAUGUGCUUCAGGGAAAAGAAAAAUGAAGAGCAUGUGCACCAUCCAGGAUUUUCCUCGUUAUUUAAAUCCCUUUAGCCCAUCUCCCAUUUGCCCCAAGGAAUGAGUGCUGGCAGUGAGCUGCACUUUUUUUUUCUCUAAACGGGAAAUGGGUUAAAAGAUGAGUGGCUUGGCCGGGUGCGGUGGCUCAUGUCUCUAAUCCCAGCACUUUGGGAGGCUGAGGCCAGAGGAUCACUUGACUUGAGCCCAGGAACUGGGGGGUCAUGCUGGGAAACAUGGCAAGACCGCAUCUCUAUUAAAAAUAAAUAAAAGUUAACUGACUGUUUAAACAAAAGUAUUAACGUAUCUGCGGUUUGUACUAUACGCACAGGUAAACUGUGUGACCACAGCAGCGUGAUGGCUGGGAGACGCUGGAUGUGAUACGUGAAGUGAGGGGUAUCACUUGAAGGUAGAUUGUGGUAAGCUAAAGAUGUACUGAUAAACCCUUGAAACACCCACUAACAAAGAAUUACAGCUAAUAGACCAACAGAGGAGAUAAAAUGGAAUUUUUAAAAAUCCAGUCCAAAAAUACGUAGAGAAAGAGGGAAAGGGAAGAAUGGACUUGGGGGCGACACAGAAGACAAGUGGAGAGAGACUGAAGCAGCCACUGGCCAUCACAGCAAACACAAGCAGGGCGCAGGACGCCGGCAAGCCACAGACAGGCCUGCUCUCUGAAUUGGUGACCACAUGAGUAACUUCACGGGUCUGUUCUAUGUCCAGAGUUGUCAAACUGCAUGCUUUAAAGAUGUGCAGUGGAUCGUAUGUCGCUUAAAUCCCAACAAAGCAGUAUUUUUUUAAAGUACAAUCAUGCACACAGCACUUCCCCUGGGAGGCAGGGGCUGUGCCCACAGAAGUCGUUACCUCUGCGUCCUGAGUAUGGACAGCCACCAUCACACAGCCCCAGAGGCCGCCCAGGCUCUAGCCACACUCUGGCACUGCCUGGGACAGGUGCCCUCAGGAACCCAAAUGCCACUGCCCCCGUGAAAGCCACUUCAAGCGUGUUGCUUCAAAUCAGAAGGCAUCUACGCCUGUGGAAGAGGAGGCUGCUGGGGGCCCAGGUGUGCAGGGGGCAGGGCCAGGUGCAGGGGCACAGCUUAUGCCUGUGGCCAACCCACUGGGGAGCAAGGCUGGGGAUAUGCCCAGGCCAGCAGGGCCAGCAGGAGUGACUGCGCCAUCCUGAACACGUCCUUGGGCCUCCCAGGACCUUGGUGCCUCCCAUCUGGGCUGGCACAAGCCUCCAGUCAAAAGAUGGGUCUCUCUCUCCUGAUAGCAUGGAGCCUGGAUGUGGGAAUGGAGCCACACCAGCCCCACGGGAGCCCCACGACCCAUCGGGCUGUGGGAUGCAUCCCCACGGCCGGGACCCCUCAGCCUGUGACUUGGUCUGGGCAGAUGCAAAGGCCACCCUGCAGGGCUGAGGUGUCUGUGGGGAAGGAGGUGCCCAGCCCUGGGAGGCCAUCUUGCUCCUGCUUUUUAUUUAACCCAUGGGGCUCUUUGGCCUCAUUUUCUGUUUUUUGAGUUUCUCGUGCACUCCAAACUGUCCUGGAGCCAGCCCUGGUGUGAAACAGAGGCUUCCUGCUGGCAGAAGAGGCCCACCGAGUUACGUCCACACCAGCUGGCCCUGGGCACCUCUCUCUCUGGCCUUCUGUCCACACUGGGAUUUGGCUCUGAUUUCCAGAAGGCAGGGUUAGGAAACACCUGUUUCCAGGCAGAGUAAUGCUUCUGUCUGAAUCAGGCCUCAUGGGCUUCACCAGCAGACACGAAGGUUUCAUUUAGAUGGCGAACACGUGUUCUCAUUUCUCCAGGGUUCUGGACCCGUGAGCUGAAGCAGGUGCUGAGAAGUGGGAGAGGCGGCCACUGGGUCCCUCAGGGUCACUCACCCCGCCACGUGAGGCCACUUCCGCCCAGCACUGGGGGCGCUGGGAGCUGAGGGGCCCACAGGGGACGUGGGAGACAGCCCCGAUGCGUCCCCAUCCGCAGUGACGCUAGCGCGGAGUCGUCGCCAAGCACGUGGAGGGACAGCCCUGGAGCCCUGGCCUGGCCCAGCAUCUCCCAGAGUCACUUCCUGAUGCCUCCCCAGCCCUGCCCAGGAAGGGUUUGUGGCCACAGCCCCACAGCGGCCCCCUCGCCUCGACCACCAGUGCCUCCUUCCAAGCUGCCUGAGCAAUCCUGGGUGGUGAGCUCCACCACUCCCACCCACGCCUCAGCACUGGGACCCCCCAGGGAUGGUGUGGGGAUUCCUGCCCCCCGUCCAUGCCUCAGCACUGGGAGCUGGGAAGGUGUGUGAUUUCCUCCCCCACCUCAGUACUGGGACCCCCAGGAAGGGUGUGUGGCCCCACCAUCCUGAAUGCUCAGGGCUGGUGGUCAGCGAGGUGGUUUCUAAACCAAGCCCUGGGAGGAGCCAUCCUGGGACUGUGCUUGGACAAGGUUGGGGCUCCCGCAGUGAGCUCUAGCCCUCCCCAGGACCCUCCCACGGCCCCAGGGUGCCGGCCUUCAGAUUGACCCCAUUCGUGGAUGAGUCUACAAGGCUCCCCAGUGCCCAGCAAGAGUGUUUUUACAUUCAGAGGUGAGGAAGGGGUGCCGGCAUCUGCCCCAGACACAACCGGGCAGGUACAGAUGUCAUCCCCUUGAGGACAGCAGGGAGGCGACUCAGGAGAGGCUGAUCAGACGGGAGCCGCAUCCCCAUCACCUUCCAGAGAGACCUCUUCUUUUGCCAGGUGUCGUGAGGGCUGUGGCUUAGCUGGGCCUGCGUCCAUCCCCGGUUCUGGGGAGAUGCCCGGGCCCCUCCUGGAUGGCAGCAGCAGUGGAGGUUUGGGUUUUGAGGGAGCCCUAAGAACCUGAGAGACUUAGAUGGAGCAUGGCACGCCCUGGAGAGUCCACGUCCCCAGACCCCUCAUGCCAACACCAUUCCACCCAGCAGUUUCUUCCCUGUGGUCAGAACAAAACCCCCAAGCCUCAGGCCUCAGGCUGGUUUUCUGACAGGCAAAAUGCUCCUUACAUAAGGAAAGACCUUUCCUUGGCUGACCCUAAAGUAGCCAAGGGGAGCUCACAUCGCCUGGCCUGCCGCCACCACCAGGCUGCCUGACCAGCUCACCGCCUUGUUCUAGAUGCUUCUGAAGCAACAGCUCGCCUGGCCCCACCCCCAUCAAGCAUCUGCUGGGCAGCCUCCCUCCCCGGCCCGCCUGUAGCUCCCAAAGGUCUCAAGCCUCAACAUCCUGGUAACCAAGUGCACCCAGAGGGCUGGCAGGGUCACAUGGAGGCAGGGGACCCUUGGCCCCAGGGUGGUCGUCUUCCCAGGAGGUCCGCCUGUCAGGUCAGAGGGCAGCAGGAGGCCACCCCACCUCCCCGGGUUCCCUCGAGCAUUCCUUUGUCAGGAGCAGCUCCCCCAGGAUCCAGGCAUCCCUGGCCCCCCUUUGCCCCCGCCCUGCUCUCAGGAGCCCCCUGCCAGGUGCUCUGACCACAGGAAACAGGAGCCCUCAGGGCCACUGCCAGAGGACGGAUUCUGCUGCCAACCAGAGGUCCUGGGGCUGGCGGCGCUGGUGUGCCUGCCCUGGGCCUUCAGCAGCCCCCAUAAGGAGAAAGCUCCAGCCUCCCGUUCAGAGAAGGCUCCAUCCUGGGGACACGCCUCUCCCAAGGUCACCCACGUGGGGGCUUUGUUACUCAUGCUUCCCAGACUGCGUGCUGUGUCAGAGUUUUCACACCUGCCUGAUGUCCUGGGGGGGCUCACAGAGGACCGACCCUGCAGGGAGAUGCUGACCCACCCUGAGACCCAGGAGAAGAAAACGGCCAGGGUCCAGGCUGCUCCCACCAUCCCUGGGGGAUUAGCACCUUGGCUGAGCCCGAACUGACCACCUGGGGCGUAGGUCCAAGAUUUAAUUACAAAACGAUAGGUGAAUGUGGGUUCUGUGUGCCUGUGACAUAGAGAAUGUUUUCCACACCGCGUGUGAAAUGACGAGAGCUUUUGUGUCACACAUGUAGCUGCUACGAGACAGACGCUCUUGUUCCGGAUCAGAGCAGCAGACAGAACCGGCACUUUUAGGGUCCAAACCCUGUUGCCCACAGAACGCCCAUGACACCAGCUGGGUGGAGCUGCCGCCGAGUCCACGCCCCGUCUGGCUGGGACCUGGAGCUCCCCUCAAGCUGCAGAUCCACUCUGCACCACAAGGUGGCCUCGCAGAGGAGCCUCCCGAGCUUUGGAACCAGAGGCAGGCUCAGCGAUGCUCUCCAUCCGGCCUGGCCCCACCGUGUGUAUCAGGUGUCAGAGGCCUUGCUGGGUGCCAGGCCACGUCUGUGCUGUCACAGCUUUGAGGGGCCAGCGGGUCCUAGGGAGAGGCCCGUGCGACGUGAGUAACAGCAGUUUUUCUUCUGACAGCUGGGAUGGAGGUGGGUCCUCCAGGGAGUGCCCCAGUCCUCGAGAGCCAGACUUGUGCACGGGCCUGGAAAUGAAGGUCUCAGGCAGGGGCUGCGCACACCGAUGGUCAGCAUUGCCGUUCGGGGCCUGCAGUCGCCCAUAAUGGGCCCUGCCCCCUAGGCCUGGCCUCUUUUGCUUUCCUCCUGGAUGGUUCCUCUACCCCUGGUCCAGCAGGGACUCAGCAGUGCCUGCCAGCUGCAGACCCCCAUGCUCCUGCAGCCUGGAACCCUCCUGCCCUCCAAAGGUCAUGGGGUGACCCAGGGUGGGAACACCAGACCCCCUCACCCCGUGUCCACCGCCCAUGGCCGGGCUCACAGUGUCUCAGAGCCGUGGUGAGCCAUCCUAGGACCAGUGUACCUCACAACCUUUCAGACCAGUGAAGGCCAGUGGGCUGGGUGGUCCAGGCAUGUCCCCAACGCAGGUCCAGCCAUCUCUGCACAGAACUGGAAUCUCGGUUCAUUUCGGUUUCAGCAGGUCCCAUGUAGUUAGCAGGACAGCACUUGAGUUAGGUCUGAGAAAGAACGCCUGUUUGUCAUGGCAUUUCCUGUAAGGAGCCCAGAGCCGUGGCCCCAGGUUGGGACGGCGGCGCCAGAGCUGGGCCUGAGUCUGACCCAACCUGUGCUGAGUGGUCCUGCUGGAAUGGGAACCCCAAGAGGACCACCCCUCUCUAAAAGAAGGGAAAACAGUAAGCGAGAGGGAGGCUGCAGGGGCCCAGACCUUGGCUGACCUUCCUAGCCAUGGUCUCCACCCUCCGAGACCCAGGGGCCCCGCAGUGACAGCAGGGUGUUGGGCCACACAGAGCCCGAGUAGGUAAAGGAAGGUUCUGGAAACCACUUUUCAGAACCCAAAAGGUGUCUGGGAAAUGGCGUUACCUGCCACUGUUGUUAAGUGUUUACUUUGUAUCAAUACUGAAUUGUUAAAAAUUUUAAUCAUAAAAACCAAUGGAACAUG